AUUCGGUGGUCAGAGGCCUGUGCGGCUGCAGGUAGAGUGUCUUAGGUGAGGAGGUACUUUUAAGCACCGCGCGAAAUGGGGGCGAAGAGAAUUUUUUUACUUUUGAGGGUGGGACUAUCCUGCAAGGUGUGACUGCGGUCGGGUUUUCCGUAGCCAGUUUCGCACCAGGGAUCCUUGGGAAGCGCUGGGAUGGUUCAACUGGGUGGGGUCAGAAGCUGCUCCCCUGCCCUUCUUUCCUAGGAACCUAGGAAAUAACUCGGAACCUGUAACGUCCCACUGGUUUGGACAUAUUCCUCUCCUGAUCUGGCCUCAUCUGUUCCAGGGAGGUGGGAUUGAGCCUAGUGCAGGCUACAGUCAAACCUCUUCUGGACUUCUGCGACAGCCUUUUAUUUGGUUUCUUGCCGCUCCUUGACCUCUAACAUUCUCGUCUCUGCACUGCAGCUAACAUGAUCGUCAAACACAAAUCAGAACAUAUGCAGUAAUGUCACCUCAAAAGAGAGUUAAGAACGUCCAGGCACAAAACAGGACUUCACAAGGUAGUAGUAGUUUUCAGACCACGCUUUCAGCCUGGAAAGUAAAACAGGAUCCAAGCAACUCGAAGAACAUCUCAAAACAUGGACAAAACAAUCCAGUGGGAGAUUAUGAACAUGCUGAUGAUCAAGCUGAAGAAGAUGCUUUGCAAAUGGCAGUGGGAUAUUUUGAGAAAGGUCCCAUUAAAGCUUCACAGAAUAAAGAUAAAACCUUGGAAAAACACUUGAAAACUGUGGAAAAUGUGGCUUGGAAGAAUGGGUUAGCUUCAGAAGAAAUUGAUAUUCUAUUAAAUAUUGCACUCAGUGGCAAAUUUGGAAAUGCUGUAAACACACGGAUAUUGAAGUGCAUGAUCCCAGCAACAGUAAUAUCAGAAGAUUCUGUGGUUAAGGCAGUCUCCUGGCUUUGUGUUGGCAAGUGUUCUGGUAGCACCAAGGUACUUUUUUAUCGUUGGCUGGUUGCAAUGUUUGACUUCAUUGAUCGUAAGGAGCAAAUUAACUUGCUCUAUGGCUUCUUUUUUGCUUCAUUGCAAGAUGAUGCACUGUGCCCUUAUGUUUGCCAUUUGUUAUAUUUACUUACCAAAAAAGAGAAUGUCAAACCAUUUCGUGUGAGAAAACUGCUUGAUCUUCAGGCCAAAAUGGGAAUGCAGCCUCAUCUCCAGGCUUUGUUGUCACUGUAUAAGUUCUUUGCUCCUGCUCUGAUUUCAGUAUCUUUGCCUGUAAGGAAGAAGAUAUAUUUUAAGAAUUCAGAGAAUCUAUGGAAGACGGCUCUGCUUGCCGUGAAGCAAAGAAACCGGGGACCUUCUCCAGAACCUCUGAAGUUGAUGUUAGGUCCAGCUAAUGUUCGUCCUCUAAAAAGAAAGUGGAAUUCUCUCUCAGUUAUACCAGUGCUCAAUUCCAGUAGCUACACUAAAGAAUGUGGAAAAAAAGAGAUGAGUCUUUCUGAUUGUCUGAAUAGAAGUGGAUCAUUUCCACUAGAACAACUUCAAAGCUUCCCCCAACUUUUACAGAACAUCCAUUGCUUAGAGCUGCCUUCUCAGAUGGGCUCAGUGCUAAACAACUCUCUGCUGCUUCACUACAUUAACUGUGUCAGAGAUGAGCCAGUCUUGCUGAGGUUUUAUUACUGGUUGAGUCAAACAUUACAAGAAGAAUGUAUUUGGUACAAGGUGAAUAAUUAUGAACAUGGAAAAGAAUUUACCAACUUCCUGGAUACCAUCAUCAGGGCAGAGUGCUUCUUACAAGAGGGGUUUUAUUCCUGUGAAGCAUUCCUGUAUAAGAGCCUUCCUCUCUGGGAUGGCCUUUGUUGUCGGUCACAGUUCCUUCAGCUUGUGAGCUGGAUUCCUUUUAGUAGCUUCUCUGAGGUGAAACCACUUCUUUUUGACCAUCUAGCGCAGCUCUUCUUUACAUCAACCAUUUAUUUCAAGUGUAGUGUGCUUCAGAGUCUGAAAGAGCUAUUGCAGAAUUGGCUGUUGUGGCUUUCUAUGGACAUUCACAUGAAACCUGUUACAAACAGUCCUCUAGAGACAACUUUGGGUGGAUCCAUGAACUCUGUGUCUAAACUGAUCCACUAUGUAGGGUGGCUAUCCACUACUGCAAUGCGCUUGGAGAGCAACAAUACUUUCUUGCUGCACUUUAUUUUGGAUUUCUAUGAGAAGGUGUGUGACAUAUAUAUAAAUUAUAACCUUCCAUUAGUGGUAUUGUUUCCUCCUGGGAUCUUCUAUUCUGCACUCCUCAGCCUGGAUACCAGCAUCCUGAACCAGCUGUGUUUUAUUAUGCACAGAUAUCGUAAAAAUUUGACUGCCGCAAAGAAAAAUGAGUUGGUACAAAAGACAAAAUCAGAGUUCAAUUUCAGCAGCAAGACUUAUCAAGAAUUUAAUCACUAUUUGACAUCAAUGGUUGGUUGCCUGUGGACGUCCAAACCCUUUGGGAAAGGAAUAUAUAUUGACCCUGAAAUCCUAGAAAAAACUGGAGUGGCUGAAUAUAAAAACAGUUUAAAUGUAGUCCAUCAUCCUUCUUUCUUGAGUUACGCUGUUUCCUUUUUGCUACAGGAAAGCCCAGAAGAAAGGACAGUAAAUGUGAGCUCUAUUCGGGGAAAGAAAUGGAGCUGGUAUUUGGACUAUUUAUUUUCACAGGGGUUACAAGGCUUGAAACUUUUUAUAAGAAGUAGUGUUCAUCAUUCUUCCAUUCCCAGAGCAGAGGGCAUAAACUGCAACAAUCAAUAUUAAAUGAAUGUUGACAUAAACUGAACACACUGGACUAAACUCACUCCUCAUUGCUAGAGCAAAGUGGCUCAUCUUGAGUUCCCAUUUUCAUUUCACUGACAGACUGCCAUCCUCAAGGAGUACUCAGACUGGCCUUCUGUUCAUGGCUUAGGAGAGCCUUGGUGUGCCUAACUGAUUUUUCAAAAUUUAGAUUUUUUUAGCCUACCAGUGAAAAAUGACCCCUUCAUCAUCAGGCUCUGCGUUCUACCAAAUUGUAUGUAAAAAGACACAUCUGUUUUGUGGUAGGAUUUUUUCACAUUUUUGGGUACUAUGAGCUGCAUUGAUGGAAGACAGCAGGCAAUAUGUGGUGACAGUUAACUCACAGACAUAAACAUGCAAAAUACUUUGCUGUCUCUGGGGAUAUUGCCAUUUUUCUUACUGUGAGCAACAGCACCAACACCAAGUUAACAGGAUGCAACAUGUGUAUGACUCUAAAAGCCCUAAGUAGUUGGUAACUUCCUGGGCCUUCAAUCAUAGCAAUUUGAUGAGGGAAGGAAGGGGAGAGGAUUUGUUGGGUAAUCAAGACAUUCCCGUAUAUGUCUGAUUUCAUGGAACUGCUCUAUUUUGUUUGUGUGUAUUGUAUAUGUAUAUGUGUAUGUGUGCGUGUAUGUGUGUGUCUGUAGCUUCAGUUUUUAAGUGUAAGGACUAAAUAAACUAACUGAAAUUUUACUUUCAGAAGGAAUUCUGAAGUUUUAAAAAAGUUAAUAAUAGCUAGAAUAUCUUGCUGAAAAUGUACUAUAAAAUUUUGCCUGCUGGGCGUGGUGGCUCACGCCUGUAAUCCCAGCACUUUGGGAGGCCAAGGUGGGUGGAUCAUGAGGUCAGGAGUUCGAGAUGAGGCUGGCCAAUAUGGUAAAACCCUGUCUCUACUAAAAAUACAAAAAAUUGGCCGGGCAUGCCGGCACGUGCCUGUAGUCCCAGCUACUCAGGAGGCUGGGGCAGGAGAAUCGCUUGAACCCGGGAGGCGGAGGUUGCAGUGAGCCAAGAUCGCGCCACUGCACUCCAGCGAGACUCUGUCUCAAAAAAAAAAAAAAAAAUUACCUCAAUGCUAUUGAAUAAUUCUCCCUUCUAGUAAAAUUCGUAUCAUUUGAGAAGAAUCAAGCUGAAUUAAUUUUUGUCUUUAAGGAUGCAUACUUGGGGUUCUUUUUUUUCCCCAUUUAAAAAACAAACCCUAAACUAUAUUAUUGGAUGGCGUUCAGACUAGAAAUCCCACUCGUCCAUUGACUCAUUAAUUGAUUCAAUAAAUAUUUAUUGAGCUCCUUUCUCUGUGCCAGGUACUCUUCUGUGUGCUGGUUAUACAGUUGUGACCAAUACAAAGUACCCGGGUUUUUGUUUUUGUUUUUGUUUUUUGAGAUGGAGUCUCACUCUGUUGCCCAGGCUGGAGUGCAGAGGCAUGAUCUUGGCUCACUGCAACCUCUACUUUCUGGUUCAAGCAAUUCUCCUGCCUCAGCCUCACGAAUAGCUGGGAUUACAGGCACCUACCACCACGCCCAGCCAAUUUUUGUAUUUUUAGUAGAGACAGGGUUCCGUCAUGUUGACCAGGCUGGACUUGAACUCUUGAUCUCAAGUGAUCAACCCGCCUUGGCCUCCCAAAGUGUUGGGAUUAGAGGUGUGAGCCAUUGCACCCAGCCCAAAGUACCUGUUUUUAUGGAGUUUACAUUCCAAUGGAGAAGACAGACAAUAACAUAUAUCAAAUGCUAUAAAGAAAGGGCAGGGAAUAGGGAUACAAUGUGUUGAAUUUUGUCAAAUGCUUUUUUUGUAUCUUUUGAGAUUAUCAUAUGGCUUUUGUCCUUCAUUCUGUUAACAUGAUAUAUCACAUUUACUGAUUUGUGUAUACUGAAUCAUCUUUGCAUCCCGGGAUGAAUCCCACUGGGACAGAAUGUGGAGAGGGUUGAAACUUUAGAUAAGAUGGUUUGGGAAAGCCUGUUUGAAGAGAUGACAUAUGCAGAGGCCCCAGUGAAGUAAGCAUAUGAGUCAUAUAAAUAUUUGGGGAAAGAGCAUUCUGGACAAAGGUAAAAAACAAGUGAAAAGGCCCUAAAAUGUUAACUUACUUGGCAUGUUUGAGGAAUAACAAAGAGGCCAGUAAGGUUACAGCAUAGUGAUUAAGAGAGAAGAAUGGUAAGAAGUGACAUAAGGAAGAAAGCCAGGUCCUUAUAGCCUGGCAUGGAUAUGUAAAUGGGAAGCAAUUAGAUUGAGAAGAGGAGUGACAUAAUUUGAUUUACCUUUAUGAAAUAUGGAGCUACAAUGUCAAGGUUAGACUGAAGAAGAUUAAAGAGGAAAGCAGAGACUGGUUAGGUUAUUAUAGUGUCCUAGGUAACAGUUUUGGACAAGUGUGAUAAAUGUUGAGGUGGGAGGGGUUAGAGGUUGGAUUCAGACUCUGUUUUGUAAGUAGAGAAGAUAAUGUCUGCUGAUAGCUUGGAUAUGAGGAGGAAAAGGAGAGGAGUAAAGGAUGACUCAGAUUUUUGACCUGUCAAUUGGGUGAACUCUGAGAUUAAAUUCUGUUUUGGCUAUGUUAGGUUGGAAAUGCUGUGUAGGCAAUUGGAUAUCCAAGUCUGGACUUCAGAGUACAAUUUGGGACUAGAAAAUUAAUUUGGGAGUCAUUAGGGAAUAACCAUGACUUUGGAUGAGAUCACCUAGUACAGCUAGAGAAGAGAAGGUAGCAAAAGACAGAGACCUAAGGUAUGCCAGCAUUGAGAAGUAGAGGAGAAGAGGAACCAGCAAAAGACUGAGAAGGACCCACCAGUGACCUAGAAGAAAAAUCAGGAGGCUGGUAUUCUGGAAGCCAUCAGAAGAAAAUGUUUCACAAAAGGAAGGUAGUAUUGAAUGGUGUGAAAUGUUACCUAUAUACCUGGAAAAAAGCAACUUCAGCUGCUUUUUAAGUAAAUGUGAUAGUUUGUACUGCAAAUAACUUUCCAUAUUGCUUUUCAGAUCAUGAUAUUUUGGUCCUUAAGAUCAUGUAGAACUUUCCAUUGUGAGAAGGGAGUUGAUUAUUUUAUCAUUAAAGAAACUUUUCUAAACUUAAAUUUAUGAAAAAUAAUUUUUCCCUUAGGUUUGUCUUUUUGUUCAAUAAUGAUUCCCUGGGUAUCUUUUUUUGCCCCACAAAUAAAAUACUUAGACAUACCUGGA